GCCAUCUUUGUUGGGGGCAGCCAGGCCUGGCUCGAGAUGCCGAAGUCGUGCGCGGCCCGGCAGUGCUGCAACCGCUACAGCAGCCGCAGGAAGCAGCUCACCUUCCACCGGUUUCCGUUCAGCCGCCCGGAGCUGCUGAAGGAAUGGGUGCUGAACAUCGGCCGGGGCAACUUCAAGCCCAAGCAGCACACGGUCAUCUGCUCCGAGCACUUCCGGCCAGAGUGCUUCAGCGCCUUUGGAAACCGCAAGAACCUAAAGCACAAUGCCGUGCCCACGGUGUUCGCCUUUCAGGACCCCACACAGCAGGUGAGGGAGAACACAGACCCUGCCAGUGAGAGAGGAAAUGCCAGCUCUUCUCAGAAAGAAAAGACUUCACCCUGCCGUUCCCAGGUCCUCCCUGAGGCGGGGGCCGGAGAGGACAGUCCUGGGAGAAACAUGGACACUGCACUUGAAGAGCUUCAGUUGCCCCCAAAUGCCGAAGGCCACGUAAAACAGGCAAUGUUGUUUAAUGUAGAAAAUGGAACCCCAGCUUCACGUGAAGCCUUGUGGUUGAGUGAGGAGUGAAGGAUGGGGAGGAGGCCUCUGGGGAAGGGGUUCCCUCCCUCCUGAAGAUGAACACACAAUACACGGAAGAGCGCCAGCCUCUGCUUUCAGGAAAGGUUUAUUGUGGUGAGUGCCUUCUGUACAGUCGACUGCAAAUGAAACGCAGAGGAUGGGUGCCCAGAAGCACCUGCGGCAGAGGCGCACGGGAAGCCCGGGGCCCAGGCUCAUGCAACACGACGCUCACCGCGGCUCGGGCCGUGGGGCCGUCAGAGAAACCUUUUUAAAAAAUGGAGAUGAAUGUUACAGAAUUGGACAACCCGAACUGCUUUUCAAAACCAGAGGAAGGAGGUUCUUAGCCGUUACUCAGAUACCAGUGCUGGGGAGGGAGGCCUGACUUCAGCAACAGCUGUGGGUGGGCUGGAGGCCGGCGCAGCUUGGGGCCCCCCGCGCCAGCUGUCUCAGCCACCACCUGUGCGGCGCUUGCUCCGAGGGGUCAGCAAGAGCAACUGAUGGCUGCCACUUCCAGGCCCCGAGAGACAGGCCUCACGUAACUUUACUGCAGCCGAGGUCCAGGCCGUGGAGGGGGUCCUAGCUCCGCUGCAUUCUGCAUCCCAAGUGGGCACGUGGAGGAAGGGUCUGAAGGAAGGCUCCGGAGCACAGGCCCUGGUGUUCCUGUGAGGACGCUGGACCUGCAGGAGCGGGGAGCUGCAGUGCCACCUGCUGGGUACCACGGGCCGGGCCUGGGGUCCACGCCUUUGGGUUGGGUGUGUCUGAUGUCUUGCCAAGCGCCUGGUCCUGUCCUCUUGAGCUGCCCUUGCCCAGCACUGCACUCUGGAGGUGGGUGGUGCAGGCGGUGGAGGGACACAGGCCAGCUCAAGCCCGCUGGUGGCAGGGCGUUUUCCCACCGGGAUACGGGAAGCCACCUGUGUCAGGGCUAGGCCCUGGGAUCGGGAGUUACACUACCCUGUCCCAAGCCGAGGGGGCCGGUGGAAUGACUUGAGCAGCUCUGGGAGUGGGGAAAAAAGACGACUAAUUUCCAAACCCGUUUGUUCUCAGAUAAAAAGCAGUUUUAUAAACCCGCAAUCUGCUCCAGAUUCAAGCAGUAAUAUUUCAGCAAGAGGAGGUGGUCAUGGGAAGCCAGCACAGCAGAGGCUCCCUGACCGGGAGGCCUGCCUGCUUUUCAGGUUGUUUCCCAUGUUCAGCGUGGACUGCAGAAGUGGCUCACGCUCCUGUGGUGAGGGCAGGGUGCUCCACAGACACCUCCAGACCCAGCCAAGAACUACAGGGCGGCGGGCUGCGGUCAGCACGUGUGCUCGGGACACAGCGGAGUCAGGGCCAGAGCCCUUCCCUCCAGGAACUGAUCCUUGGGAAAACAGCCAUGGGCCAGGCUGCAGUCUGGUUCCCAGUGGGGCUGCCUCAGUCCUACCCCCAGCACCCUCAAAAGCUGGGGUGUCUGCAUGUCCCUUCACAUAAUUGAUAAUGGUACCACCUUCUAUAAUAAUAAUAUAAAAUAAAAACAUCUGAUGUC